AGCCCAGGAGUUGGCGGGUAUGUAGAGAGAGGUGUCAAAAAUAGUAAUUGAGAGUGAGCUUUGGGAGGAAGAUGUUGGAAAUAAAGAUGGUGGAAGAAAGAGGAGUGCUGAGGAAAGGUGCUCUGAAAGAUCGUCCUGGUGGGAGACACAUGGGGAUCUAGAGUGGAAAUGUUACGGGAUCUCUGGGGUGUUGAUUUUUCUGGCUGGAAACCUCUGCGGCCGCAGCACCUUUGCCUCAGUUCUUGUCCUGCAUCCAGGAAGAAUGAGGUACGCAGAUUAGUGAAGGGUGAAGAACAGUUUUAUUUAGUGUUAGAACAGCUCAGAGUAGUGGGUAGCUCCUCUCUGUAGGCAGGUCAUCCGUCGAGUGUUCAGCUGUCAGCAGAGGAGGCCCUGGAGAGGGUGGCUCCUCUCUGCAGGCAAGUCACUUGGACAUCUCUGCAGGUCUCUGAAGCUCUCAGCAGAGAGCAUAGAUCCUCUCUGCCCUCUCCGUCCUCUGGCUGUCCUCUCGCCUUCUCUGACUGAGCCCAGGGCUUUUAUGGACCUCAAGAGGGAAGGAAGGAUGUGCCAAUUGGUCCAUGGGUGGCCAUGGGCGGGCCUGGAAUAGGUACCAUGAGUCCUCACUCUGGUCCACAGGACUGGCAGCCCAGCUGCCAGCCUUCAGGCCCUUCCUGGCCUUCCACUGUCCCCUUCCACUCAGGACUCUGUCUGCCUCCCGCUGCCAUUCAUGGCCCUGGGGCUUGGCUCCAAUCCCACUCUGAGAUCCGAGUGGGUGCUGGGAGCUGAGAGAGGCCAGGCAGUGGAAGCAGACACCCAUGACCCUGCAGGGAUGGUGUGGGGGUUGUCCUUCCUGGGGCGCCUGAGGGUGCAGGCUGCAGAGUGGGAGGGCAGCUACAGCUGCACCCAAGAGCUCCCGACCCACCACCUCAGAAGAGGCCAGGCUCCUGCUUGUUCCCGGCUCCUGCCUGCUUCGUGGAGCAGGAAGCCCAGGUCUGCAGCCACAGAUCUGGCGGCUGCAGCUGCACGCGGAAAGGCAGAUCCUACCUGUUCCCGGCUCCCCUAAGAGCACCGGGAGACGCAGAUCCACAGCUGCAGUUUGGGCGGCUGUAGCCCCGCCCUUCUGGAGCAGGAGGCCUGGGUCUGUAGCUGUGACCCUGUGUCUGGGCUGCAGCGGCCACUCUACCUCAGAAGGGGCGGGGCUCCCACUGGCUUCAUGGAGUGUGCAGCCACAGCCAGGGUUCCCUGCUGCAGCCGGCAUGAUGGCAGCAGCCACUGCCAUCAGAACCUCCCUGGGAGCAGGGAGGACAGGCGUGGGAGGACGCUUAUUCAGUGGCUUCUUCCAGGGAGAGGUUCUCGAGAUGUCCUUAAAGGAGGUCUUCAUCCUCUGGAAAGCCUUUGGGUGGAGGAAGUUUGGAACUGUGCCCUUGAGCAGGGACCCUGUUGUGUAGGAGGGAGUAGGAUGGUUUCGGGGGAAGACGUUGGGUGGCGUUCCCUGCAGAGAGUAGGAUGGUUUUGGGGGAAGACGUUGGGUGGCGUUCCCUGGAGAGAGUAGGAUGGUUUUGGGGGAAGACGUUGGGUGGUGUUCCCUGGAGAGAGUAGGAUGGUUUCGGGGAAAACAUUGGGUGGCAUUCCCUGGAGACAGUAGGAUGGUUUCGGGGAAAACAUUGGGUGGCGUUCCCUGGAGAGAGUAGGAUGGUUUCGGGGGAAGACGUUGGGUGGCAUUCCCUGGAGAGAGUAGAAUGGUUUCGGGGGAAGACGUUGGGUGGCGUUCCCUGCAGAGAGUAGGAUGGUUUUUGGGGGAGGACGUUGGGUGACGUUGCGCUGAGUGUUUUGGGUUUGCAGUUGGUACUGAUCAUCGCGUCCUGUCCUCAUUUUGUUGGAAUUAAAAAUACGUUAAUCACAGAGGUCUGGUAAGUUUCCAGAGGGAAGGUCUCUGAAGUGGAGCUGGGUACUGCCCCAGGGUUUUGGUGGGGUUGGUGAGCCGUAGUGGUGCAGAGGGUGGGCUCUGGCACCAGGUGGCCCGGGCAGGUCCUGGCUCUGCAGCUCACCCGGGCAGCUGUGGGCUGGCAGCCUCCUCUGUCUCACCCUUCUUACAUGUAAUAUGGGAGUCAUAACAGUAGCCACCUCAUGAGGUUGUUAUAAGGAUGAAGGGAGUUAAUCCACAUCUGGCACACCCAGCAGUGCCUGGCGCCUGGGCAGUGCUCAGCCGCUGCAGCCGUUCUUGGUGGGAGUGGACUUGACUGCUCACAGUUGGAGCAUGUUGGAGUGUGUUCGUUCCCUGUUAUGGCUGUGACAAAUGACCACAAGCUUAGUGGCUGACAACAACAGAUUUUCUGACCUCCAGAAACGACAAUCUGGGGGUCAGAUGUCCAAAAUCAGACUCACCGGCUUAAAAUCAAGGUGUGGGUGGGGUUGCUUCUUCUGGAGGAUCCAGGGGAAAACCCAUCUCCUGGUCUUUUCCGGCUCCUAGAGGCCACUGCUUGACUUGUUGCCCUUUCCUCUGUCUAUGAAGCCAGCCGUGUUACGUCUUCAAAUCUCUCCCCUCGGUGACCUUCUCUGACUGACCCUCGCAUGCCCCCUUAUAAGACCCUUGGGUUAUCACCUGGGUCAUCCAGGGUCGCCUCCCCAUCCCAGGAUCCUUAACUUCAUCUCAGCUGCAGCGUCCCUGUUGUCCUGUAAGGGAACAUUCACGGGCCUUGGCGAUUGGAUGGCUGCGCUGGCAGGACUGUCACUCAGCCUGAUGGAACGCCUGGCUGAGGAGUACGGCGCGAGGGUGGUGCGGACACUGACGGUGCAGUACCGCAUGCACCAGGCUAUCAUGCGCUGGGCCUCAGACACCAUGUACCUUGGGCAGCUCACAGCCCACUCUUCCGUGGCAAGGCACCUCCUGAGGGACCUCCCAGGUGUGGCUGCCACAGAAGAGACGGGUGUGCCCCUGCUCUUGGUGGACACCGCCGGCUGCGGGCUGUUUGAGCUGGAGGAGGAGGACGAACAGUCGAAAGGGAACCCUGGCGAAGUCCGCCUCGUCAGUUUGCACAUCCAGGCUCUGGUGGACGCUGGUGUUCCAGCCCGUGACAUUGCUGUGGUCUCGCCAUACAACCUCCAGGUGGACCUGCUCAGACAGAGCCUUGUGCACAGGCACCCUGAGCUUGAAAUCAAGUCUGUCGAUGGCUUCCAAGGCCGAGAGAAGGAGGCCGUGAUACUGUCCUUCGUCAGAUCCAACAGGAAAGGUGAAGUUGGUUUUCUUGCUGAGGACCGGAGGAUCAACGUGGCUGUCACCCGUGCCCGACGCCACGUGGCGGUCAUCUGUGACUCCCGUACUGUCAACAACCAUGCAUUUUUGAAGACCCUGGUGGAGUAUUUCACACAGCAUGGGGAAGUACGCACGGCCUUUGAGUAUCUUGACGAUAUUGUCCCAGAAAACUAUUCCCAUGAGAACUCCCAGGGUUCCAGCCACGCUGCCACCAAGCCCCAGGGACCUGCUACGUCCACCAGGACCGGAAGCCAGCGGCAGGAGGGAGGCCAGGAGGCUGCAGCACCUGCCAGACAGGGCCGGAAGAAGCCGGCUGGGAAGUCUCUGGCCUCUGAAGCUCCAUCUCAGCCCAGCCUCAACGGAGGCAGCCCAGAGGGAGUGGAGAGCCAAGAUGGCGUGGACCACUUCCGGGCCAUGAUAGUGGAGUUCAUGGCCAGCAAGAAGAUGCAGUUGGAGUUUCCUCCUUCCCUCAAUUCCCACGACAGGCUGCGGGUCCACCAAAUAGCCGAGGAGCACGGGCUGAGGCACGACAGUUCCGGGGAAGGGAAGAGGAGGUUCAUCACUGUGAGCAAGAGGGCCCCGCGACCCCGAGCAGCCCUGGGACCCCCAGCAGGGACCGGUGGCCCAGCCCCUCUCCAGCCAGUGCCCCCUACCCCUGCGCAGACAGAGCAGCCUCCCAGGGAGCAGCGUGGCCCAGACCAGCCUGAUCUGAGGACGCUGCACCUGGAGAGACUGCAGAGGGUCAGGAGCGCGCAGGGGCAGCCCGCCAGCAAGGAGCAGCAGGCCUCAGGGCAGCAGAAACUUCCAGAAAAGAAAAAGAAAAAAGCCAAAGGACAUCCGGCCACAGAUCUGCCCACGGAGGAGGACUUUGAGGCCCUGGUUUCUGCCGCCGUUAAGGCUGAUAACACCUGCGGCUUUGCCAAGUGCACAGCCGGCGUCACAACCCUGGGCCAGUUCUGCCAGCUCUGCAGCCGCCGCUACUGCCUCAGCCACCACCUGCCCGAGAUCCAUGGCUGCGGUGAGAGGGCUCGCGCCCAUGCCCGGCAGAGAAUCAGCCGGGAAGGGGUCCUCUAUGCCGGCAGCGGGACCAAGAACGGAUCCCUGGACCCAGCCAAGAGGGCCCAGCUGCAGAGGAGGCUGGAUAAGAAGCUGAGUGAGCUCAGCAACCAGAGGACCAGCCGGAGGAAGGAGAGGGGGACGUGACCGGCCGCAUCCUUGCACGCCCCGCGGAGCUCUCUCCAUGGUAGCCCAGGGCGCUGGCAGACCAUGCUCCGCCUCCACCAGGGCCACAGAGGAGCGGAGGGGCCUAUGGGGGAGGAGCGGAGGGCCCUGUUGGGGAAGGUUGGGUUUUUGGACCCCAGGGAUAAGCUUUUCCGAUGUCACAAUGUGGAGGAAAGCACCUGGGGGACAACAGUGCUCGUGCAGGUGGGGCUUGGGAAAUGCACGUCCCUUCCCCUUACUCCCCGCCAAAACCCACAUCCCAGCCUCUGGAUCCUGGGGAAGGUUCCAGUCCCUGGAGAAUACCCAGGGCCUCAAACUUGAAGUCACUCCUCCAAUGUCUGGGACUUGCCAGCUCAGCCCGUUAGGAUGAGGGUGCUGAGAGGAAACAGGAAACAAGACUGCGAAUGGCGCUCAGGCAGGGAGCAGGGAGUGGCGUUUGGCUUGCACGUUCCCAUGUGGCCAGAUGCUGGGGCCACUUUCCUUCUGUCUGCUGGUGACUGCAGUGUUCCCCCUCCUCCUCACCACGGGGCUCCUGUGAGUCUGGGGGGCACCUCUUUCUGGCCUGUGCACCUCUCUCUGGCUUAUAAAGGUGCCUGGCCUGUGCCAGCCCCUCCUUGUUGCGCCUCACCGUGGGGACCAGGUGAGCCGGCUCUCCCACGUGGUUGUCCCGGGAAAGCUGCCCCACAGCCUCAGCAUCUUCAGCACUUACCGAUCCAGAGCCUCCCGGCCUUCUCCGGUGUCCUGUACCAACUCUUCUAUUUAAGAGAACCUCAGAUGAUGUACCUGAGCCUCAGGGUUUUGUUUCAGAGGGAUAUAAAUUAUUUAAAAAUUAAAUGAAAACGUUGCACACUG